AGAGCCCGGCCCAGGCCGCGGAACGGUGAUGCUCGGGCCGGACGGGCGGGCGCGGAUCCCUGCGUCCCGGUGAGCACCAGGCCCGUCCAUCCGGGGCUCUUUCCCGGGGUCCCCUUCCUUCCCUCCCUCCCUGGGGCUCCCCUCCCCUCUCUCCCUCCCCGGGGCUCACCUUCCCUUCUUCCCUUCCCAAGGGUCCCCUUCCUUCCUUCCCUCCCUCCCUGGGGCUCCCCUCUCUCCCUCCCCGGGGCUCCCAUUCCCUUCUUCCCUUCCCAGGGGUCCCCUUCCUUCCUUCCCUCCCUCCCUGGGGCUCCCCUCCUCUCUCUCCCUCCCUGGGGCUCACCUCCCCUCUCUCUCUCCUCGGGGCUCCCCUUUUCUUGCAGGUAUUGUCUCCCGGGGUCGGGUGGUCUGUGUGGCCUGGGGUCCCGCUCCUCCAGGCCUUGCCUAGGCGCUCUUCGCUGAGGCCCACGUUCUAACCUGGAAUGGAACCUGCGUUCCCACCCUGGCCGCCCGGGUGGACUCGGGGCCUCCAGGGCCGGCCGCAGAGAUGCAGCCCUGUCCCUGGCCCCCCUCCUGUGACUCCUAACGGCUCCUCACGGUGUCCAUGACCCAGGGUGUGGACGCCUGCGCGGGGGAAGCAAGACCGCUGCGUAUCGGGUCCCUAUUCACUGCCUGUUUUUCUGAUUAUUCUGUCUUCCAAAUUUAUCUUAUUUACCGGCUUUUUCAAAAGGAGUGUCUUAAUGAUUGGAUUACUUGUGAAAUAUUUGUAGUUUUUUUCUCCUACAGGCUUGACUUAAAUAUUCUAAAGCUUUUUUGUGGUUGUUGAGACAGAGUUUUGCUGUCGCCCAGGCUGGAGUGCAGUGGCUGGUCAAGGCUCAAGCGAUUCUCCCGCCUCAGCCUCCCCAGGAGCUGGGGCCACAGGGAGCAUCACGCCCGGCUAAUUAUUUCAUUUUUAAUAGAGACAGGGUCUUGCUGUGUUGCCCAGGAUGAUCUCCAACUCCUGACCUCAAGCAGUUCGCCCACCUCAGCCUCCCAGAGCGCUGGGAAUACAGAUAAUUGUGUCGUAAUACAGCAGUGGCAUUAACCACCGCACCUGGUCUUAGGUAGAAUUUGAAAACCUUUUUAUUUUGAGAUGGUUGUAGAUCACAUGAAGUUGUAAGGAGUAAUACAGAGAAAUCCUACAGAGUGCCUUUGCCCUGUUUUCUCCAAUGGUAGCACCUUGCAAAACCAUAGUAUAUGUGGGGAAUUUUCUUUGAUCAAAUCCCCUGACCUGUUGAGAUUGCACCAACUAUACAUGCACUAGUGAGUGUGAAUCUACACCUGUGUGUCUUCUCAAUAAAAUUGAGAUUUUUUUUCACUCAGCCUUGAGAUACAUCCGCAUUGUUAUGUGUAUCAAUUGCUCAAGAUGCAGAAAUUCUAAGAAUUCAUUAUUUAAAAAGUAAUCCCAGCACUUUGGGAGGCUGAGGUGGGUGGAUCACCUGAGGUCAGGAGUUUGAGACCAGCCUGGCCAACAUGGCAAAACACCGUCUCUACUAAAAAUACAAAAAUUAGCUGGGUGUGGUGGCGAGCGCCUGUAAUUCCAGCUACUUGGGAGGCUGAGGCAGGAGAAUUGCUUGAACCCGGGAGGCAAAGGUUGCAGUGAGCUGAGAUCACAACACUGCACUCCAGCCUGGGUGACAAGAGCAAAACUCCGUCUCAAACAGCAACAACAACAAAAAAAACACAUUACAGGAAUCCAAAGUGUCUUUUUAAUAACUAGAACAGCUAAAGAUGUUUACUAAUUUGCUCAAAAAACAUGCUACAAUUUAGUAGUCAGUAGGAUUUUGGAGGCAAGUUUGAAGAUAAAAUGAAAUGAGUUUGAAUAAAGGUGAUUUGUAUUUUAAGGGUCCAUAAAUAAUUUCAGUUUCAUGUUAUGAGUAUGUUUCAGUGGGAAAUUUUAGUAUAACUACAACUAAAAUCCUCAAAGGUUUCUCAUAAAAAUUAUAGCUCCCUUAGAGGGACAACUAAUUUUAGGAACCUGAUUGAGGAAGGAACCAGAAAUGAACAUAGAGGUGUCAUUCACACAUGAGCUGUGUUGAAACUUAUUUUUCUGAAGCAUAAAAUCCAUCAAAGAAUCACUUUUUGGGAUCUUUUGGGGAAACUGGGAAGUGUAAGCAAAGCAUCUCAGAUUUCUGUCUUGGUUCUGGAAAAUACUAAAAGUUCACUUGUGAAGUAGCUGUUGAUUUAUUUAGCUCCGUUGGACCAACCGAGAGAAGCUUAGCAGUUGAGUGAGUCAUUAAAAUAACAGCUCAGCUAUAUGGCUAGGCAUGACUAAGUGAUUGCCUCAUUGUUUGUUUUUAAGGUGGUAAAUGUGUACUUAAAGUUGUACACGUGUACUUAAAGUUGUAUUGAAACUAACAUAAAAUUGAGUGAUUGGAACAGCACAUUAUCAUUUAUCCUAUCUUGUUAGGAAGUUACCUGUUCUAGGUAAGUGAAUUCUCUGUGGAGUGUGCUUCUCCUUUUGGGAGUCAGUCUCCAAGAAUGUUUUGAAUUGAACACUUUCUAACCAGAAUAUAGUCUUUUCUUGGUGACUUUUGCUUGUAAUUCUGAUCAGUACUGUUGUCUAACACAGUACUGUCUUCAGGACCUGCUGGGGUGCAGACAGUCGCUGAGCCUUCACCGAGUCAUCUGGCCUCCAGGCUUUUUUAGUUCUCCUGUUUGUUUUGCAUAAGGUUUGUCUCUUUCUGUGGCUGCCAUUUCAUGGUUUGGGCAGAAUGCUGCCUCCAGAAAUGCUGCCCUUACUUUUGCUGCAUCUAACCUACUUUGCCUGGGAAACUCGAUUAAACCAAUUAGAAUUUGGGUUAGCAGUGAAAUGAAAGUAUAGAUAUAUAGAUACAUCUUUUAGUAACCAGGUUUCCAGGUCGGGGAAUCUUUGUAAUAUGUGAUGGUUGAGUAGGAAUUCCUGAGUAACAGUCCAUUGGAUGCUGCUAUGAAGAAUGGUUAGGUUAAUAUUUUGUUGUUGUUUACUUUAAACUGUAAAUCUGCGUAAGUGGUAGGUGUUGGUUUUGUUGCCUUUUUUGGGAUAGCUACUUGUGACUGGUGAUCUCCUAGUGGCCAAAUUCCACGGACUCUACGUUUAUUACUCCUUCCUUCCACGGUCUCGGUUUCCCACCUCUCAGCUCGUUCUGCCUUAGUGACCUUUGCUGGCCGCUGUCUCAUCCUGCUUUCUGAACAGUGCUCCUGUCUGGGUGCCUUGCCCUACCCCUGCUCAUCACCACCUGGACACCACGGCUACAGCCGCACUGAAACCGUCCUCAUUCCCCCAGCAGUAAUGUUCAGAAAGCAGGUUCCUGUCUGUGCUGUGCCUUGCCAGGAUAAAUUAAUAUACAUUGUUUUAGGUAUUCCUAAAGAAAGGAAGAGAAGGAGACUGAAUUGGGAUGAUAACAAAAAGUUCUAGAGAUCUAGCUGAAAAUGUGUGUCUGACAUGCAAGCUCAGUGGGGCAGAGACCCGUGGAUUGCUGUGCCCUGCCCUCCGGACCUGGAUCAUGAAGGUGUUGGGAAGAAGCUUCUUCUGGGUGCUGUUUCCCGUCCUUCCCUGGGCGGUGCAGGCUGUGGAGCACGAGGAGGUGGCGCAGCGUGUGAUCAAACUGCACCGCGGGCGAGGGGUGGCUGCCAUGCAGAGCCGGCAGUGGGUCCGGGACAGCUGCAGGAAGCUCUCAGGGCUUCUCCGCCAGAAGAAUGCAGUUCUGAACAAACUGAAAACUGCAAUUGGAGCAGUGGAGAAAGACGUGGGCCUGUCGGAUGAAGAGAAACUGUUUCAGGUGCACACGUUUGAAAUUUUCCAGAAAGAGCUGAAUGAAAGUGAAAAUUCCGUUUUCCAAGCUGUCUACGGACUGCAGAGAGCCCUGCAGGGGGAUUACAAAGAUGUCGUGAACAUGAAGGAGAGCAGCCGGCAGCGCCUGGAGGCCCUGAGAGAGGCUGCAAUAAAGGAAGAAACAGAAUAUAUGGAACUUCUGGCAGCAGAAAAACAUCAAGUUGAAGCCCUUAAAAAUAUGCAACAUCAAAACCAAAGUUUAUCCAUGCUUGACGAGAUUCUUGAAGAUGUAAGAAAGGCAGCGGAUCGUCUGGAGGAAGAGAUAGAGGAACAUGCUUUUGACGACAAUAAAUCAGUCAAGGGGGUCAAUUUUGAGGCAGUUCUGAGGGUGGAGGAAGAAGAGGCCAAUUCUAAGCAAAAUAUAACAAAACGAGAAGUGGAGGAUGACUUGGGUCUUAGCAUGCUGAUUGACUCCCAGAACAACCAGUAUAUUUUGACCAAGCCCAGAGAUUCAACCAUCCCACGUGCAGAUCACCACUUUAUAAAGGACAUUGUUACCAUAGGAAUGCUGUCCUUGCCUUGUGGCUGGCUAUGUACAGCCAUAGGAUUGCCUACAAUGUUUGGUUAUAUUAUUUGUGGUGUACUUCUGGGACCUUCAGGACUAAAUAGUAUUAAGUCUAUUGUGCAAGUGGAGACAUUAGGAGAAUUUGGGGUGUUUUUUACUCUUUUUCUUGUUGGCUUAGAAUUUUCUCCAGAAAAGCUAAGAAAGGUGUGGAAGAUUUCCUUACAAGGGCCGUGUUACAUGACACUGUUAAUGAUUGCAUUUGGCUUGCUGUGGGGGCAUCUCUUGCGGAUCAAACCCACGCAGAGCGUCUUCAUUUCCACGUGUCUGUCCUUGUCAAGCACACCCCUCGUGUCCAGGUUCCUCAUGGGCAGUGCUCGGGGUGACAAAGAAGGCGACAUUGACUACAGCACCGUGCUCCUCGGCAUGCUGGUGACGCAGGACGUGCAGCUCGGGCUCUUCAUGGCCGUCAUGCCGACUCUCAUACAGGCGGGCGCCAGUGCAUCUUCUAGCAUUGUCGUGGAAGUUCUCCGAAUCCUGGUUUUGAUUGGUCAGAUUCUUUUUUCACUAGCGGCGGUUUUUCUUUUAUGUCUUGUUAUAAAGAAGUAUCUCAUUGGACCCUAUUAUCGGAAGCUGCACAUGGAAAGCAAGGGGAACAAAGAAAUCCUGAUCUUGGGAAUAUCUGCCUUUAUCUUCUUAAUGUUAACGGUCACGGAGCUGCUGGACGUCUCCAUGGAGCUGGGCUGUUUCCUGGCUGGAGCGCUCGUCUCCUCUCAGGGCCCCGUGGUCACCGAGGAGAUCGCCACCUCCAUCGAACCCAUCCGCGACUUCCUGGCCAUCGUUUUCUUCGCCUCCAUAGGGCUCCACGUGUUCCCCACGUUUGUGGCGUACGAGCUCACGGUGCUGGUGUUCCUCACCUUGUCAGUGGUGGUGAUGAAGUUUCUCCUGGCGGCGCUGGUCCUGUCUCUCAUUCUGCCGAGGAGCAGCCAGUACAUCAAGUGGAUCGUCUCUGCGGGGCUUGCCCAGGUCAGCGAGUUUUCCUUUGUCCUGGGGAGCCGGGCGCGAAGAGCGGGCGUCAUCUCUCGGGAGGUGUACCUCCUUAUACUGAGUGUGACCACGCUCAGCCUCUUGCUCGCCCCGGUGCUGUGGAGAGCUGCAAUCACGAGGUGUGUGCCCAGACCGGAGAGACGGUCCAGCCUCUGAUGGCUCGGAGAUGAUGGACCGUGGAAGGGAAGCGUCUGUGGGGAGUGAGCGCUUAGAUGGCCAGCAGCUGCUCCUUCUGGGAAGCUCGCACCUUGGCAACAGAACAGCCCUCUAGCAGAGCGUCAGUGCAGUCGUGUUAUCCCGGCUUUUACAGAAUAUUCUUGUCCUAUUUUAGAAUUUUCCGGAGUAGUUUAUUUGCAGUCUGUUGAUUAUGUGCAGUAGACCCGGGACACUGCGUUUUACCGAUCACCUUGAAUGUGGUGCCUGGAUGUGCCUUUUUUUUUUUUCCCUGAAAUUAUUAUUAAUUUUCUAUUGUGAGUUCAUCAGUUCAUAGUUUUUUUAGUAAAGAAGCAAAAUUAAAAGGCUUUUAAAAAUGUACAACUUCAGAAUUAUAAUCUGUUAGUCAAAUAUUUGUUAUUAAACAUUUCUGUAAUAUGAAGUUGUAAUCCUGGCCGUGAGCUUGGAAGCUUACUUUUGAUUCUUAAAGCCUAUGUUUUCUAAAAUGAGACAAAUACGGAUGUCUAUUUGCCUUUUAUUGUAACUUUUAAAUGAAAUAAUUUCAUGUCAAUUUCUAUUAGAUAUAUCACUUAAAAUAUUUGGUUUUAAAUCACAAGAAUAUGUAUUCUUUAAUAAAGAUAAUUUAUGAUCAUGGUAUAAUUAAUUGAAAUUUAUUAAAAUCUGUUUUUAUUAA